GGAGGGUCCGGGCAGUUUUAGUAGUGUCUUUGGGACAACGGCUGCGGAUCACUGUAACUGCUGGUGACGACUGGAUUAUAGGAGGGCAGGAAUUGUGAGAAACCACUCAGAAGGCUACUGCUGUAGAUGAGCGAUGUGACCUAGCGUAUGGGAGAGAAGUGGACGAAUCAAAAGUAUAUUUAGCAGUAGAAUCCUGCUUAUCUGUGAAAUGCAGUUAACACAUCAGCUGGACCUAUUUCCCGAAUGCAGGGUAACCCUUCUGUUAUUUAAAGAUGUAAAAAAUGCGGGAGACUUGAGAAGAAAGGCCAUGGAAGGCACCAUCGAUGGAUCACUGAUAAAUCCUACAGUGAUUGUUGAUCCAUUUCAGAUACUUGUGGCAGCAAACAAAGCAGUUCACCUCUACAAACUGGGAAAAAUGAAGACAAGAACUCUAUCUACUGAAAUUAUUUUCAACCUUUCCCCAAAUAACAAUAUUUCAGAGGCUUUGAAAAAAUUUGGUAUCUCAGCAAAUGACACUUCAAUUCUAAUUGUUUACAUUGAAGAGGGAGAAAAACAAAUAAAUCAAGAAUACCUAAUAUCUCAAGUAGAAGGUCAUCAGGUUUCUCUGAAAAAUCUUCCUGAAAUAAUGAAUAUUACAGAAGUCAAAAAGAUAUAUAAACUCUCUUCACAAGAAGAAAGUAUUGGGACAUUAUUGGAUGCUAUCAUUUGUAGAAUGUCAACAAAAGAUGUUUUAUGAAAUGUCAGAAAUAUUAACAAAAAUUCUCAGCAUUAAAGAAAACAUUGAUUUUCCUUUCCUGACUAUAAAA